GCAUUGUUCGGGCGACUCUCGGAGCGCGCACAGUCGGCUCGCAGCGCGGCACUACAGCGGCCCCGGCCCGGCCCCCGCCCGGCCCCGGCGCAGGCAGUUCAGGGAAGCCCACCAUAAUGAGAAGAGCGGGGCCAACACCCAUGUCACUGUGGAGAAGUACAGAAUAUGCAAUGGAAGAGUUGUUUAUCUGAUAUAAGCGGUAAUUGGAAACUGAAAAAUUCCUGCUCUGGAAAAAAGAUAUUCUGCUCUUCUGAAUCUAACAGAGGAAGAGACAAACAGAAACCAUCAAUUAUUGUUUCAGGUAUACCCAGAGUACCAUCUGUACCAUAAACUACAACUCAACUGUUGAAAAUCAUAACUUCCAUCAAAAUUCUAACAGCUGUGUUUCCCAGUGUCUUUUAUUUUUUUAAAGCAGGCAAGCAUCGAUUUUUUAAAAUUUAAAAAUAACACUCUUUAAUAUUCCACACUUUUUCCCAUUUAUUAACUUUAAAGCAUGGUUCAAAGAACAAUCACAUAAGACCUCUUUUAAAACUGAAAGCUAAGUAUGACUUAUCAUGGAUACCCUAUCUCACACUGGGCUCUUUGGAUGAGCAAUUUCUUAGUCCUUGGGACAAUCUGUAUGAUGGGAAAAUGUUUUUGAUAGAAUGAAUGUGAAUUUCUACACUUCCAAAUAAAGCACAUAAUAAUUUUAUGCUUAGUAAGUUCAUUUGCACUUUUGUGGUGAUUAACCUUAACUGUUAAGCCCUGGUAUUUUUGUGCUAUUUUCCUAAUGCUGUGAUGGAGACUAUAGUAACAGCCAGUAUGAAAACACAAAUCAAGCCUUGACUUAAUUUUCCGGUUCUCUUGCAGUUCCCAUUAAUUUGCCUUCUCAAAAGGCUGUAAAUUUUGUUUAAGGGUUCUCUGCUGUAAUUUCCCCUCCAAAAAAGUGCCUUUGGUAAUAAAUGGAUUUUGAGAUUUAAGAAAAAAAACUGAAAAUGUAGGAGGAAGAAUAAGAUUCCAAUAAUUCUGCUUAGGUCAUGUUCUGUCCAUGUCUAGUGCUUCAGGGCAAAGUGAACAUUUUACAAGGUGAAUAGAAAAAAAACAUACAGCCCCUCCUAUUUAAAGGAAAAAGGAAGAGGGGCAAGAAGAGAACUGUUUAUAAAAGACUGGAUAUUGUGGAUGUAAGGCAAUAUUGGUCUCAACCUGCUUCAGGAACUGAAAUGGCCCCAUCUGUUGUUCACAGAGCCUGUCAUCUUUGAAAAAUCUAAUACACCCUACCUUAUCUGUUGGACAUAUUAAUUUUAAACGAUUUUAAGGUCCAUUUAAUUUGUAUUUGACCAUGAAUUCAGCUUCAAUUUAAACUGAUUGUUUAGUUUUUGUAAAUUAUAUUUAAAUAAGGAUUUAAAGAUGAAGAGACACUGCAUAUGCAGCCAGCAUCACAAACCUUCAAAGCAAUAUUUCUGUGGUUGCUGCUGUCAUCACCACAACAUUUUCUAGCCACCAACCCAGUCACUUAUGCUUAAAGUGUGCUGCAAUGACUUUUAGAACCUCCUAUGGCUGGUCAUUUUCUACUUAAAAUGAGGUAGGACAUUCAUGUUUUGAGUCAUUUUGUUAGGUACACUAAUUCCUAGCAGAUUAUCACCAACACUUAUCAGCCUUUGCACAUCCCUCCUUUUUUUAAAAAAAAAAAAAGACUUGAGAUUCUCCUUGACCUUCAUCUGCACUAACAUCGUCUCUGCCUGGGAAAGCUGGGCAAACAAAAAUGGGAAGGCUUACCAAGGAAAGUCCCUGGUUUCUUUUUCAGAUAUGAGAAACACUCCCUCUUCAUGCUUGUUCUCUGAGAUGCUUUAGCAGAUUAAGAUAGGACAGCAGCAGUUUUAAUUCUGAGCCCAAGAACGAGAACACAUUAGCAGUAUUCUUUUUCCAGUCUGACCGUCCUCACAUUUCUAUGCUCUACUGGCUCCAAAAUAUGAUAAAUUGUUAAGUAUAGAAUUUUUUUUAAACAAGCUUGGGGAAUGAUGUGUUUGUGGGGGCAGGCAGGGGAGCAGUAGGGAGGUAAGUAGAGGAGUAGAUAGGUAAGUGUAUGAUUGGGACAGACAGGAUGCAGACAUACCUCAACUCCUUGUGUCUGUUUAUGAUAACUACUUAUUCUAGCCUAAAGGAGUUAUUAUCAGCAAAAGAAAGCAUACAUUACAUCAGAACAGCAAACAUUCAACUAUGAAUUUGAGAAGUACCUUGAUAAGGUACUUGACUAUAUGGAAAAUGGGAUACCCCAGGCCCCACAGUCACACACACACACACACACACACACACACACACACACACACACACACACACACAGUCCUGGCACAGAAUAUCCACAGAAUUUUACAGCUGGAAGGGGCAAUGGAGGUCAUCUGAUCCAAAUGCCUCACUUUACAGAAGAAACUGAUGUCCACAGUGUGACUUGCCCCAGAGACACAGCUAUGCAGAGGUAGGGCCAGGGCCCCCUGCAUUCUUGGGCUACAGCUCACCAGUAGUUUUUCCUUAAUUAGUGCUAGGAAGAGAGGAGAACAGAAGCCCCAGAAAAAGCCUCAGUACUGUAGGUGUUAAUUUAGAUAUAAAAUCCAUUAAAAAAAGAAAGUAGAAAGGUUCAAAGUUCUUAAGUAUAAGCAAUAAAAAAGCAAAGGAUAAGGAAGCAUUGUGAAAAUCAAUACAAUUUAAUCAGGCUACAACAACAGAAGGGAGGUGAUAAAGGGAGGAAAGAGAAAAUAAAAAAUAAGUGUAUUUAAAGGUCCUCCGGCUGGCAAAUCCCACUCUCUACUUGGAAGGUGAGAGGUGCCCUGGAAAGACUGUGUACUCUGUGGUCAAAGACAUUUGGGUCUGAACCACUAACUUGACAAAUGACCUUCUAUUAGUAUCUUCCAGCUAAGCAUUUUGCACUCCUCAGACGUCCGCAGCUAGCAGGAUCCCUUUCAAAAUUCAAAGUGACUCAAUGCCUUCAAAACAACCUCCCCCAAAACUGCAGAGGAAGUCACCUAUGAAGGCUACAAGCUCCUGGUGGUACUUACCCUGCUUUAUUUUCCUUCAAACUGUGCACUGUGAUGUGACAUUAAAUUACUCAUUAAUGAUUUAUUUGCUUAUUAUCUGUCUCUUGGACUAUAAACUCCUUCAGGGUCAGUUUUACAACCAGCUUUACCUCCAGUGCCUAGGAAAGUACCGAGGUACAAUUAGUAGGUGUGUUGCUGGGACAGAAAAGGUGUUGGAUAAAUAUAUGAACAAAUUACAACCUAGAAGCUGCUUAUUUGAUACAAAAAAAAAGUGUUUCUGCAAACAGUGGGCUGUGGAGGGCCCCUUCUUCUAGAUUUUGUUUAGGAGCUGAAAACAAAUCUCAGCCACUACUUAAAGCAACCAUAUGGAAGUGACUUACAGAAACCAGUUAGGCUCAGGUUAAGUCAAGGCAGUGAACUUAACUAGAAACCAAGUUAGGCUCAGCUUAAGUCAAGGCAGUGAAAUCUGCUUUGUAUGGCAGUGUAUGUUAUAUAGGCAGACUAAGUCAGAUGCUUUUCUGCCCAUCUUCAUCUACCUCAGUUUAAUUCCCUCCCCAAUAAAAUGAGACUUUGUAUACCUGGUGAAGGAGUAUCAGGUGAGUCACCCGGGGGCAUGGAAUGGCCUUCAAGCAAAAUAUGGAAGAACACAGUGCAGUGGUUAAUGAAGGGUGGACUCCUCUGAAUUUCUCUAAUCUCUGUGCCUCAGGUGAAGGCCUGGAAGAUGCACUUACGGGGCACAAAUGGCUUAUCUUUGCCAUGCAGCAGACUGCCUUUUCCCAAGCAUGUACUUCAUUCCAAAGUUUCUGUGGGUAAACCAGUGUAUCUCCCAGAUUUUACAGAAGAGUGAUUUUUCUUUAAUUUCAAAGUUACUCCAAUGUCAACCUGUGAAGCUAGCCUAGGGCUUAUAAUUCUCCUCAGCAGUAGCAAACAUUUACUGAGCUAAGCACAAGGCAUGAAAACAGGCCCAGCAACUAAGUUCACCACACACCAUACCAUGUCACUAACCCAGCUAUAGCUACUAGCAUGGACUGGUACCACAUUAAUGACAAGGACUAAGAUCACUAGCAGCUCUUGGACAACAACUUCAAUUAUGGUCCCAUCCCUGCUCUAUUUUAAUUGACUGGUAAUGCAAUGAAGGUAGGAGAGAUCAGCUACACAUAAAAACUAAGUAAAGAUAAACAAUGUGGGAGAAUGCUUAUAAAAACUUCAACAGAAUAUAGUCAAUGGCCAACCUUGCUGAAUAGUGACACUGAAUUGACAGGGAUAAAUGUUAGUGUCUCAACGGUGAGACUAAAAGAGUAAGAAUAAUGGGUGGAUAAAUCAGAGUUCUACUCUUCUUAGCUCUGCCAUCCAUUUACUGGGUGAGCCUCCUGUUCCCUUGGUUUCUACAAAUUACAAAAAGGGAACAAUGUCAUCCACCCCAAGUAUUUCUCAGUACUCAAUAAAGAUUGAAUAAUGAGCAAUAACCCUCAUGGGAACUCUGAUCAAGUAGAGAAGAGACAAUAUAAAAAUAAAAGCUACUGAUUAUAUCACUACAGAGACAAAUUAGCUAAAGAAAAUGAGGGUAAUUUGAGGGAAAGAGUCCACAUGUAAAUGGAGAAAAGAUGAACACAGCUGUAGCACUUGGGCCUGUGAGAGCUCCAAAUCACUGUAUCUAAAGCAGCCUCAAGGCUGAGGUCAGUCCUCUAAGAUGGGCUGCCCUGACAGAAGCAAAUCUGCCAGAUUUAUUGUGUCUCAUGGCCCACCAGUCCUGGAACAAAAGUUUAAAGGUGAAAUAUGUUUUUCUCUUUCUUUUUAAAAUGCUUUUUUAUGUGAAUCAAAACAAAAACAAAUCUCUGAGCAGAGAUCAUAAGUGGAAUGUAAAACAUCACAUUUGGGCUCGCAAGACUUAAGUGUCUGCCUGUUAAAUUUGAAGAAAAGGAAGGAGUUGCCUGGUCCAGGAGCCUAGAGAGAACAUGAGAAAGUUGCUGGUUUCUUGCUGAAGACAAACACCCAUUCAGUGAGAUAUUGUGGAAGUCCCUUAGUCUUAACUUGUUAGUCUGUUAAUUGGGAAUGGCAGAAGAAGUGAAUUACUCUGUGGAAUUUUGUGAAAAUGAAUCCACUGCUGCUAAAAGGAAAAUUAUCUACUUUUCAAACACUCAUAUUAUUAAAAUAAAUACAUUAUGUUUGAAGUCGCAUAUUAUUCUUGAGGCUUUCAAAUAAAAGUGAGAGUAACUUUGCCAAGUGAUUUGGGGCUCCACUAAUCUCCCCCCAAAUUCUGCCCCAUAAAAUUCUUUUUACAGUUCAAUAAAAUUCAUUAGGCUGAACACAGAUGCAAAGAAUCACAGGCAAAGUUAAGAUUCUCUGGCCAAUUUUCCCCAUCUGGACUUUAAUUAAAUUUGUCUCCAAGUGAAUUCUUCUCUUCACUAAAUGGUUCUCCUUCCAGAAGUGACAAGAACAAGAGGAACAAAACUCUACUUGUCCUUCUUCCAUUCUAAUAACAAGUCAUUCUGAGAACUUUAGGUACCACUCAGCCUAAGGGAUGGUUAUACUCCCCUAGGAAGUGGUUCUUUUUACCUCUCUAUCAUUUGGUCAAGUAUGCACAGAGUUCAACCCAUAUGAGGGAUACAGAGGUAUUAUUCCUUUAAGGAGCUUACAGUUGGCUUAACGGCAAAAGUAAUAUACUAAAACAAAUUAGAAAGCAGUACAAAAUAAUGUAGAAUAUUUAGGUAAUAAAGCUGUAAGGGCUGUGGGGACUUAGAAAAGGAAAAUCAGCCAGGGUUAGACAAGUUAAGAAACAUUCAUGGAAAAGAUGGGAACUGAAAUGUAAAUGGAGAUGACUGAAUGCAGCAUUCCAAAAAAGAUGGCAGACUUAUUCUUCAGAAGUCUAUUAUGAAAGGAGAACCUGAGGUUAAAAGACAAAUAAGGCUUGUGCCAAGAUCAGAGCACCCAAACUGUAAGUUUAAAAACCCAUUAUUUGGCCUUCAGAACAACCUGGACUUAUGCAGAAAGGAAGGCAGCUUAAAGUAACAUCACUUCUUAACCUGAAGCUUAAACGUGAUGAAGCAGUUGGCACAGUGCCAAACCUAUAGCAGCUACUGUUACUCUUCUGGUUAUGCUAGUCUAUCCAUAGGGAUGAUGCUCCUUCAUCAUCUGGUGCUGCUGGGCUGACAUAUAGGGGGCUGUCUCAGGCCAAAGAGGAGGUCCUUUGUAGGAUGCAGUCAUGAAGAAUUCCUGUUCUCAGACACCCAGCUGUGAAGUGGAGUAAAGGAUUAAGCUUGUUGAAGAUCUGUCUCUAGCGUGCCUAACCUUAGCCACUCUGUAAGGAGAGGUUACCCUUUACCUUGAUUUCCCUGCUACAAGGCAGUCCCUCCUGUGAGAAACCCACAAGAACUUUCCUAAAAAUGUCUUACUCAUCUGAAGUAAGAAACAACUUCCUGAGCAGGUAAAGGACCGAAGAGAGCUGGUGACUGCAAAAGGCUUAAAAGCUAGUUUGGAAUCUCCCUGUUUUACCAUGCACCCACAAAAAACAAAUCUGUAAGACAAAUCUUUACAACCUGGGCUAAAUGGCUUAUAUCAGAUCCUAGCCACAAACAAUAAAGAGUCUCUUUUGAAAUUAACAGUCUAAAUACUUUUUGCCUAGGUGUUAAUUUUUCAGUUUAAUUGUACUUUGAAUUUAGUAUAACAUUUUAAGUACUUAUUUGCUUUUACAGCAUACUUACAACUUGUGAACUACAACAGACUCAAAUAAAUCUGAAUCCCAUGGAAUUCCAAUUACGGUUUUCCAUUCUUUUGAACCAUUGAGACUUGAUGAGCCAUAAAAUCUCUUGACAUGUGAAUUUGUAUACAGUGUUAUAUAGGAAAGAAGGGAGGAAAGGACUCUAAAGAUUGUUGGGAGUAUUUAUUUUGUGGAACUGAGAUUUGAGAUUGCCAAAGGCUUUGUAGACCUUAGAGACAAAAUUGCACUGCUCUUCCCAUGUUGCAGCUAAGGUGACAAGCAGAUGAGGUAAGGUCAGAUAGUUAAGUCACUAGCAGAUUUUGGUCCAACAUUUCCUGUCCAUCAGAUAUGUGGCUUUUCAAUUGUUUAAUACCUGGGGUUCUGCUUUCUUUGUUUUUAGCUGUGAAUUAGUAAACUUUAAAAAGCGAUGAAUAGUGAAGCCAGAGCUUUUUUCAAAAACCUUUUUUUCAGCUACUAAAACCUGAGAUAGUUUGCCUUCUCUUAAAAUUCAAAUCACAAGGUAAGAUAUGGUCAGGGCAAAAAUGGAUGGUAUUCAAAUAGCACAUACAUGAGGUAUACUAUAGCCAUUUCUUUAACUGCCACAAACAGAACAUUUCUCACAUAGAUAAACUAAAUGGGUGAAACUCCUGCUCAGGGACAGUAUAAGCAGCAGACCCAGGGCCAAGAGAAGUGGGGUACAGUCAUUGCUCUCACCUCUAGCAGAUAUGCUGUUGACCACUGUCAUAUUUUGAUGGAAUUACUCCUUGCUAUGCAAGCUUAAUAUCCUCUAGAACAUGUUCAUCUUAAAAGAACCCAACUUACAGGAAAGGAAGUAUGAUCAGACUGUUUAUGCAUUUUCUGUCUUCUCAGUAUUCAGAAGUUGCUGAAAAGGAAAACAUAACCCAAAUGCUCUGGACUUACAGUCAAGGGAAAAUUAAACAAGGCUCAGAUAACCAAAAUAAUUUUAAUUUGUACAAAGCAUGCAAGAGGACAAGCAAAACACAGACCACAAGAAAAAUGGUCAUUCAUGUUCCAGCAGAUUACAGAAUAAAACUUUUCCACCUGUCUGUAAUUAGAGAUGGCAUAUGGCCCAAACUCUCACUUUGCAAAAAUCAUGGAAAAGAUAUAAACCAAUCAUCCUCAGGAACUAGGAAGAGUGGGUAAAGGUAGAAGUAGGAUGCUCACUGUGGCUCAUGAUUUAAUUGUUUACUCAGCAGGAAGCCAAGCCACACAUUAACCCUCAUCCUCUAACUGCCUGAACCUCUAAGUACUCUUAAAUGUAUUAAAUUUCCCUAUUUUCCUUGCUCCUUGUUUACUGAUUUAUGACAGCUAAAAUCGAGGACCCAAAAAAGUCCUCUAAGGAUCAAAAUGUUUCACAUUUUAUACUCUUCAGGCUGCUAUCCAUCCUGUUUCUAUGGCAAACUGUGACUUCAGUAGUCACAGUAAAACAUAGGCAUCUGUUGUUGUGGUUUCUAAAUUUCUGAAGUUUGAAUUUCCCACUAACAAGUUAGGAAACGUUUGGUUUCCCAAGCAUACCACUUUAGCCACUGCCUCUGUGUAGGCAGCCAGACUACAAGGAGGUGAAAACCAGUGAACUUAUCCAUUCUGGUACGUGACUGGCCCCUGCUUUGGCUUUUUAUUAAAUGUGGUGAACUGAACAACAAUUAAGGUAAGAAAGCCACAUAAAAAAGGAAAGCCUUUAAAAAAAAAAACACAGGCUUAAAAAAAGUUUUAACUUUUUGCUCAGAAUAAGUUCUGGAAAAGGAUACAUGCUUUCUACAAAGGAGAGAAUAAAGGAGAGAAUAAAGGAAAGAAAAGCAGCCCAACGAAGAGUAGAGGUUAAGAGAAGGAAUCAUAUUAAAUCCUCCAAAAUGCCCACGUGCAAUAUCUAAGUGAAAAUAACCUGUGACCUGGGAAGAGAAAAAAGGGACUAAUGGAGGUUAAAAACAAAAUUUAACAGCUACAUUGGAAUGAUUUUCUAAAGAACCAUUCCUGGAUUCUUUAAUCUGCUAAAAUACAAAAGGAUCAUUGAAAUAUAAAUGGAUUGUGAGCAAUAAAAAAACAUAUAAAUAUUCUUAAUAAGAUAAAAUACAUACACACAUAUUUCUAAGGAUAUAUAUAUAUAUAUUUAUUAUUAUGCCCUUGAAGUCUGUCAGAGAAAUGGCUGCCUGUUAAAAAUAUUUUCCAAGAACUUUAGGUUCCUUGAAAUGUUCUAUGGAAAUGGUAUUUAUGACAAACCCACCACCUCUGGGGAACAUGAGAUGUUAUUACUGGCAAAGUCACAAUUUUUUAAACCAUCCAAAAAUAAUUAUGAAUUUAUGCCAAAUGACGAAACUUGCUAUAUUAUUAUAAUGACUAAGAGAAUAUUUGCUAAUGUCUCAAGAUCAAGGCUCAAAGUAGCCAUGAACCUAUAGGAAAUACUGUGACACAACACUGAAUUGCUAGUGGUGGUGAUUUGGGAUCUUUGACAGGCAGAAUAUUACAGCACACAAAUUCACUGGAGAGGAUGGCUCAUGAGAUAUAAUAUAUGAGAUAGGAAGUGUGGAUGUAUGUAAUGGGGUGAGAAACAGGAUUUGGAGUAAAAACUACACUGGCAUUCUGGCUCUGCCAAUUACUCACCAGGACCUGUGGCAAAUUAACUUUUUUGAGCCUCAGUUCUUAUUUGUAAAAUAAGAAGACGGUAAUACCUGCCUCCUAUGACUGUUUGCAGGACUAACACGGUACAUGGCAUAUAAAAAUUGUUCAACUAGCUGUUAUUCCUAGACUAUAGAGAGGAGGGCCUACUAUAUGUCUAUUGCUUAGUUAUACCCAUGCUUUCAAAUAUGGUACCUAUUUCAAAAAUAGAAGAGGUAUUUGUUCAAAUAUUUAUUGAAUACCAAUUAAGUACCAGGUACUGUUCCCUACCAGAAAUAUAGUAUUAAACAAAAUAGACCAAUGAUUGACUAAUCAUUGAAUGAGAUGCGUGUGUGCGCACAUACACACACACCAUUACCUGCAUGUAGUUUACAUUCUAGUAGGAGAGACAGUAAUCAAUAAAUACAUAAAAUAUAGUAUGCCAGAUGGUACUAAUGAGGUGAGGGGGAAUCCAGUGGUUCCUGGGGAGACAGCGAGCACAAAAGCACACCAUGCCGUGUUCUGUUUGAGGAAUAGCAAAGAAGCUGGUGAGUGGGCAGAGGAGCAGAGUGAGCAAAGAGGAGAACAGUAGAAGGGGUCAGGGAGCCAAGUGGGUGGAGCAGAAAGCAUGGGAAUGAACAAAUGAACACCAAAAACAUGGUAUGGGAUAAGAGGAAACUCUUCUGAGGUCAACAUUUUUUGUCUGGGGUUUCCGGCAUGUAGCCUGGUUGUUAGGUAGAAAGAACACAGACUUCGCAGCCAGUGAAUUUUUAUUCUGGUCUGUUACCUGUACUGUUUGGAAAAUUAUUUAACCUCUGUAAAUUUUAGUUUUUUGGUUUCUCCUCCAUCUGCAAAAUGAGAAUAAUAAUACUUAGCUCAUACAGUUGCUAUAAGUAUUAAGUGAGAUCUAGUGGCACAGAGUAGACCUUCAAUAUGCUUGUUUCCUUCUCUUUAUAAGCCAAGUCUCACACUCUAGUACCAGUUCCAGGGCCACCAUAAUGAUGGCCUUGCAUAGUAUUAAUCUGCCUGGGCCUCAGUUUUUCAACUAAGAAAAUAAAUGCAUGUGCUCUACACAGACAUUAUAAAGAUAGAUAUACAACACUCAAGCUGUUGUUAUAAGUCAAAUAAUCUUACUGUUACAAUCUAUCUUAAUAAUUUCAAAACAGCAAAAGUAUAUGUCUUCCAUACCUCCUACAUAUUAAUUCCAUUAAAAAUAGAUCCUACAAAGUUUAAUUUCUUUAGCAUGAAGUUGUAAAGAUGUAUUUAGCAACCAUGUUUAUUUUUAUUCCCUUUUCCUGCUCCUGCUUAAGAACACUGAUCCAAUGGAAAGAUCUCCAAGAAAUGUUUGGCUGCAAAAAACAAGAUGCUGAGGAACAGUGUUUAUUAAAGAAGCUAAUUGAUCAAGAAAUCAAGUCUCAGGAGGAGAAGGAGCAAGAAAAGGAGAAAAGGGUCACCACCCUGAAAGAGGAGCUGACCAAGCUGAAGUCUUUUGCUUUGAUGGUGGUGGAUGAACAGCAAAGGCUGACGGCACAGCUCACCCUUCAAAGACAGAAAAUCCAAGAGCUGACCACAAAUGCAAAGGAAACACAUACCAAACUAGCCCUUGCUGAAGCCAGAGUUCAGGAGGAAGAGCAGAAGGCAACCAGACUAGAGAAGGAACUGCAAACGCAGACCACAAAGUUUCACCAAGACCAAGACACAAUUAUGGCGAAGCUCACCAAUGAGGACAGUCAAAAUCGCCAGCUUCAACAAAAGCUGGCAGCACUCAGCCGGCAGAUUGAUGAGUUAGAAGAGACAAACAGGUCUUUACGAAAAGCAGAAGAGGAGCUGCAAGAUAUAAAAGAAAAAAUCAGUAAGGGAGAAUAUGGAAACGCUGGUAUCAUGGCUGAAGUGGAAGAGCUCAGGAAACGUGUGCUAGAUAUGGAAGGGAAAGAUGAAGAGCUCAUAAAAAUGGAGGAGCAGUGCAGAGAUCUCAAUAAGAGGCUUGAAAGGGAGACGUUACAGAGUAAAGACUUUAAACUAGAGGUUGAAAAACUCAGUAAAAGAAUUAUGGCUCUGGAAAAGUUAGAAGACGCUUUCAACAAAAGCAAACAAGAAUGCUACUCUCUGAAAUGCAAUUUAGAAAAAGAAAGGAUGACCACAAAGCAGUUGUCUCAAGAACUGGAGAGUUUAAAAGUAAGGAUCAAAGAGCUAGAAGCCAUUGAAAGUCGGCUAGAAAAGACAGAAUUCACUCUAAAAGAGGAUUUAACUAAACUGAAAACAUUAACUGUGAUGUUUGUAGAUGAACGGAAAACAAUGAGUGAAAAAUUAAAGAAAACUGAAGAUAAAUUACAAGCUGCUUCUUCUCAGCUUCAAGUGGAGCAAAAUAAAGUAACAACAGUUACUGAGAAGUUAAUUGAGGAAACUAAAAGGGCGCUCAAGUCCAAAACCGAUGUAGAAGAAAAGAUGUACAGCGUAACCAAGGAGAGAGAUGAUUUAAAAAACAAAUUGAAAGCGGAAGAAGAGAAAGGAAAUGAUCUCCUGUCAAGAGUUAAUAUGUUGAAAAAUAGGCUUCAAUCAUUGGAAGCAAUUGAGAAAGAUUUCCUAAAAAACAAAUUAAAUCAAGACUCUGGGAAAUCCACAACAGCAUUACACCAAGAAAACAAUAAGAUUAAGGAGCUCUCUCAAGAAGUGGAAAGACUGAAACUGAAGCUAAAGGACAUGAAAGCCAUUGAGGAUGACCUCAUGAAAACAGAAGAUGAAUAUGAGACUCUAGAACGAAGGUAUGCUAAUGAACGAGACAAAGCUCAAUUUUUAUCUAAAGAGCUAGAACAUGUUAAAAUGGAACUUGCUAAGUACAAGUUAGCAGAAAAGACAGAGACCAGCCAUGAACAAUGGCUUUUCAAAAGGCUUCAAGAAGAAGAAGCUAAGUCAGGGCACCUCUCAAGAGAAGUGGAUGCAUUAAAAGAGAAAAUUCAUGAAUACAUGGCAACUGAAGACCUAAUAUGUCACCUCCAGGGAGAUCACUCAGUCCUGCAAAAAAAACUAAAUCAACAAGAAAACAGGAACAGAGAUUUAGGAAGAGAGAUUGAAAACCUCACUAAGGAGUUAGAGAGGUACCGGCAUUUCAGUAAGAGCCUCAGGCCUAGUCUCAAUGGAAGAAGAAUUUCCGAUCCUCAAGUAUUUUCUAAAGAAGUUCAGACAGAAGCAGUAGACAAUGAACCACCUGAUUACAAGAGCCUCAUUCCUCUGGAACGUGCAGUCAUCAAUGGUCAGUUAUAUGAGGAGAGUGAGAAUCAAGACGAGGACCCUAAUGAUGAGGGAUCUGUGCUGUCCUUCAAAUGCAGCCAGUCUACUCCAUGUCCUGUUAACAGAAAGCUAUGGAUUCCCUGGAUGAAAUCCAAGGAGGGCCAUCUUCAGAAUGGAAAAAUGCAAACUAAACCCAAUGCCAACUUUGUGCAACCUGGAGAUCUAGUCCUAAGCCACACACCUGGGCAGCCACUUCAUAUAAAGGUUACUCCAGACCAUGUACAAAACACAGCCACUCUUGAAAUCACAAGUCCAACCACAGAGAGUCCUCACUCUUACACGAGUACUGCAGUGAUACCGAACUGUGGCACGCCAAAGCAAAGGAUAACCAUCCUCCAAAACGCCUCCAUAACACCAGUAAAGUCCAAAACCUCUACCGAAGACCUCAUGAAUUUAGAACAAGGCAUGUCCCCAAUUACCAUGGCAACCUUUGCCAGAGCACAGACCCCAGAGUCUUGUGGUUCUCUAACUCCAGAAAGGACAAUGUCCCCUAUUCAGGUUUUGGCUGUGACUGGUUCAGCUAGCUCUCCUGAGCAGGGACGCUCCCCAGAACCAACAGAAAUCAGUGCCAAGCAUGCGAUAUUCAGAGUCUCCCCAGACCGGCAGUCAUCAUGGCAGUUUCAGCGUUCAAACAGCAAUAGCUCAAGUGUGAUAACUACUGAGGAUAAUAAAAUCCACAUUCACUUAGGAAGUCCUUACAUGCAAGCUGUAGCCAGCCCUGUGAGACCUGCCAGCCCUUCAGCACCACUGCAGGAUAACCGAACUCAAGGCUUAAUUAACGGGGCACUAAACAAAACAACCAAUAAAGUCACCAGCAGUAUUACUAUCACACCAACAGCCACACCUCUUCCUCGACAAUCACAAAUUACAGUAAGUAAUAUAUAUAACUGACCACGCUCACCCUCAUCCAGUCCAUACUGAUAUUUUUGCAAGGAACUCAAUCCUUUUUUAAUCAUCCCUCCAUAUCCCCCAAGACUGACUGAACUCGUACUUUGGGAAGGUUUGUGCAUGAACUAUACAAGAGUAUCUGAAACUAACUGUUGCCUGCAUAGUCAUAUCGAGUGUGCACUUACUGUAUAUCUUUUCAUUUACAUACUUGUAUGGAAAAUAUUUAGUCUGCACUUGUAUAAAUACAUCUUUAUGUAUUUCAUUUUCCAUAACUCACUUUAAUUUGACUGCAACUUGUCUUGGUGAAAUACUUUAACAUUAUAAAACAGUAAAUAAUUUGUUAUUUUUACCAUUGCUUGCUGAAUUUUCUUUUGGUCAUUCUGUGUUAUAUUUCUGCAUGUACAAUAGAAUUUUGUCUUUUGCUUAUAGUCUCUAUUAAUUCUUCCUUAAAAACAAACAGGACCUAUGUCCCAUUUAUGGUCAACUUCUAAUCACAUAUUAGAGGAGAGAAAAGUGGUUCAAAUAAAUAAAAAUUACAUCUCUUUGAUUUCAAA